GGUGUGCCACAUACAAGGCAGAAAUAUAAUAAUUCAUGGGUACCUAGAAAGGAACUUCAAAACCAGUAAUAAGGCAUUUUAUUCUAUUUUUAGCAUCGUCAGCAGGCAGAAGAUGGUUAGAUAAGACCAUUUGAUGAUUGUGGUGCAAAAGAUACCCUAGGGGCAAGAAAUAAAAUAACUGUAGUAGAAACCAAAAGAAUUAUUUGCUGGGAAGCCACUGGGGAGAUUCCCUUUCUUAAAUUGUCUUCUGAGGCAGAAAUGUCUGAGGUAGAACAAGCAGAGCUACACACAGAGAAUUUUCUGGUUCUAUCCACGAGAAAGCCCUAAAGGAACUGUAAGGGGCAAUCAGAGAAUAAAUCUUUGGCCUGUCACUAUGAACUAUGCCCGAGUCAGAGAUUGCCUGUGUCAUUCCCAUUUUAUAAUAUUAAGGAUAUUAUGAAAGGCAAAGUGGAUAUGGGGAGGACCAGGGUGAUUACAAGGUCCAGGCAGUGCAAGAACCCCUAACCAUCCUUCCUACCUCUCUUUGGGAAGUACAAACAAGUGGUACCCACCACAUUUAAUUAUCAAGAAUUAUCCAUCUCUUCCGAAAGUGAUGCUAAGGCUCAACUUCAGAAACAAAUCUUGAAGGAAAGCAGAAAAAUGGUUUUCUCCUCUCUUUAAAGUGGUAAUAAUGAUAAUAAAUAACAAAUUAACUACUAUAUACUAAGUUAUUUCCAUGUAACAGAAUGGUGUACAGGUUUGUCCAAGUAAGACUGCCCAGUUUUGAAUCCUGGUUUAGCCACUUCUUAGCUAGUUGACCUUAAGCAAGUUUUUAAACUUCUCUGGGCCUCAGUUUUCUCAUCUAGAAAUAAUAAUGGUAUCCAUGUUAUAGGGUUGAUGUGACAUAAUUCAUUUAAAUAGCUUAGACUAAUGUUUGAUCAAUAGUAGGACCACAACAAAUAGUUAUUGCAACUAUUACUAUUAAGUACUUUACAUUUGUUAUCCCAUUUAAUUUUCAAACAACCCUUUGAGUUAGGCACAUAUACUAACAAUAUCAACAGUUAACAGACUGAGGACAUUGCAAUUCAUAGAAUUAAAUGUGCCCAAGAUCACAUAGCUAGUUAUUACUAUAUAUUUCAGAACCAGAAAGGCUUGACAAUAUAAACUCAUAUUUUAUUGAUAGUCUGAAUGCAUGUUGAAUUUGAUUUUAUAUGGCAAAAUGGCACCAUUUUACUAUGCCUAUAAAAUUUUUGACUGAAGUUGGUUCUUCUGCUGGGUUCACUCUGUAAGAGGAAGAAUUUGGAGACAGUGAAACCAUUAGCAACCUAUUGUAAUAACAGUUGUAAAGAGAAAAUGCCCUGAUUCAUGGGAAAAUUCAGACAAAAAAGACAAGCAAGAGAGACAUCCCAAAGUGGAAGUAGAGGCCUAAAGAGAAGGAGUCAUCAAAGAUCGCCCAUUUUAAUCCUAAAGAGCCCAAUGGAUGGUGGUGAUUGGCAUAAACAGGGAAGCCAGGAGGGGAGUUGACAGUGGGAAAUUCACUUUUAGCUGUGUUUUAAGGACACAUGAUAAGAGGAUGGAGCAUGGGAUGAGUGCUGUGGGAACUGGAGAUUCCGCCACUAACAUUUUUGUUCCUCAAUUUCCUCUUUCAAAAAUGAUAAGUUGAUCUAGAAUUAAUCCUUUGGAUUCCUUCCAACUUCCUAGAGGAAGCAUGUAAAUGAAUUAGAGGAAGUAGAAGGUAGAUUUCAGGAAUUCAAGAGGCAGUGAGUGAUCAAGGUAUUGGAUCAUUAGUCUGGCCUUGAAGUAAAAGAGAGAAGUGGGACAAUUACUUACUUUUUAAGAUUAAGACAAAUGGUGCCUUUUAAGAAAUGACUUAGGCAGGAUUAAUUAAUACACCCAUAUGUAGAAUACAGGCUGUUGACAAUUAACCUAAGAAAUCUAAAGUAAAAUGUGUAACAAUGAAAGUCAAGUAGACUUUAUUUAUAGGAGAGAUAAGCUUCAGUUUGUGUGGUGUGAUAUGAAGGUGUUGGGAAAGUCCAGCUGCCCCAAAAAUGUCUUCCUGAUCUUCUUAAAAUACUGCCUGGCUUUACACCAUUAAAAUAAACCUCUUUAAAUGUACUUCAUAAUAUAAAAUGCACAUUUAUUUCACAUUCAGCUGUUACCAUGCUUUCCGGUGCAUUAGGGUAACAGGAUGACAACUAGCUACGGCGAACUGAGGAGACAAAGAUUUGAAGGGGGAGGAGGAAGGGAUUCCUUUGGUAUUUGGUGCAGCAUUACUCAAGUCAGUCAGUUCAACAACAUGUGGCUGCCUAUUAUACUCCAGAUAUUGAGCUAGGUUCUAGACAUUAAAAGGCAAGUAAGUUGUGGUUCAUUGCCUCAAGAUGCUUAUGGUCAAGAGAGAGUGGACUACAUAAAGGUCAUGGGGCUGGAGGAGUUUUGAAAAGUGGGACCAGCGACUAGGUAAAAAGGAAGAGGGACAAAGAAAUUUGUUCUCUUCCAUCACAACUUUGUUGAAGAAUUAGAUACCCCAAACAAUGCUUUUUCUUGGUCCCAGUGAAUCCCCCUAAGGAACUACUAAAAUUUAAGCUGGUAGAGUUGACACCCUGUAGGCUGAAGAAUAACAGAUAAUUUGAAUAUCUUUAACUCAAUAUUUUUGGCCCUUUGAAAUUUAAAUUAGUAAAAUUUUACUAUAUCAGAACUUGUAACCUAAACAGUUGACUAUAAAAUACAGGUUUGCUGAUAAUUUUUCCUGCUCCCUUUCUCCCCUGGAACUUCACAGUAUGCUAAGAUUGCUGAGGACUGGUGGGGGGAUCCAGGGCUAGCAGAAGCAGGAAGCAGGAAGCAGGAAAUGUAGAGAAAUUGGAGCUAGAAAGAUAACUGAGCACUUCUUUAAACAGCAGACUAGAGGAGCACCAUAUCUUCACAGAUGGUGUUAAACAAGCAUCAUAAGACAUAGCUUCAAAUAAUGCAGGGAACAUACAAUUAGGGCCACAAAAACUUGGGGUACCAGUUCUAGUUCUGGUAUUUACUAGCUGGAUAGCCACAGGAAGUCAUAAUUUUUUUUUGCCUAUAUUUAAUGAGUACUGUCUAUAUGCCAGGCACCUAUAACAUGUCUAUAAUUGACUGAAUGUUCAUGGCUCCCCUCAAAUUCAUAUGUUGAAAUCCUACCCUCCAGUGUGAUGGUAUUGGGAGGUGGGGCCUUUGGGAAGUAAUUAAGUCAUGAGAGUGGAGUCCUCAUUAAUGGGAUGACUGCCCUCAUAAAAGGAACCCCAGAGAGCUCCGAGGCUCAGUGUCUUUUCACUAUGUAAGGAUACCAUGAGAAGUCAGCACUCCAGAGGAGGAAGAAAGGCCCUCAGCCAACCCCUGACUGUGCUGGCACUCUGAUGUCAUACUUCCAGCCUCCAGAACUGUGAGAAAUGAAUGUUUGUUGUUUAAGCCACCCAGUUUAUGGUAGUUUGUUAUGGCAGUCUGAACUGGGCAAGAGUGUUUUACAUAUGACGAUAUUUCAUUCUCAUGACAACCCACUGAAGUAGAUUCUAUCAUUUUUCUCUAUUUUAUAGAUAAGAAAACUUACCCACAGAUAAUUCAAGGUCAGAUAAACUAAAAUUUGUUAAAGUAGGGAUUUGAAUACAGGUAGUCAAACUCUAAUGCCCAUGUUUAAUCAUUAUGAUAUCCCAGGUAUUAAGUCUUUUGGGCUUCAGUUCCCUCACUUAAAACUGGACACGUUGCACCAAACAAUGUUGAAAAUUCUUUCUGGCUUUAAACACUAUGAUUCUAAUUAUAUAAAUCAUAUCUAUAUUUAAUACGCUCAUGGUUAAUCUGUGUUUCGGAAUAGUCUCAGAGAACUGAGAGCUGAAGACAAGUUUCUGAAAUAUGGCUUCAUUUCUUAGUUAUCCCUUGUUUCAGUCAACGUAAACCACAUAAUUUACUCUUCCACCAAGAAUACCCUUCCUCCAUUUCCAUCUGUUGAAAAUCUAUCCAUCCUUCAAGUGCCAGCUGAAAUGCACCUCCUCUAAAUAGCCAUUCUCAGUCUUUGGGGAUUUAAAGUGCGGAUGUAUUAGACUGUUGGGCGUUGGGAUUUGGGCGAAGUAUCUGUGCUAAUGAAAGGAAAAGAUGUAGGAUAAGAAGAAAGGUUGCAGGGAACCACGUACAGGAAAGGUAAGAGAACCGUCAGCAGUGUUGUUGGUGACGGGCACAAAGCCUUCCUUGUGACAGGCAAUAGCAAAGUCACCAGAUUAUAUUAAAUGUUGCCCAGCUAGUAGGAGUGAGAUGAAGAUUAAAUGAGAACGUUUGUAAAAUAUCUACUACACUGUCUGGAAGGGCAGCAACAGGAUAAUUCCUAAUCUCUUCCUUCCAUAGGCAACUGGUCAUCUCCUUCAUGCUGAAGAAAGCUGCCAUCCUGCCCAGGGAGGAGUAGGACAAGAAGAGGGGAGAAGAGACUCUGGGGGGGAAAAGAAGUCAGGCGGAGAUAUAUGGGAACACAAAGAAAAAACGAGAGCCAGAGUACACAAGACGAGACAGAAAAAAGAAAUGUAAGGGAGUGACGGCGAAGAAGAGGAUAGAACGGUAAUGGAAGCAGAAGGGCAAAGAGGGACAAGUAAGAAGGAGAGAAUUCUAGGCCUCGGGAAGAGAAAGUUCCUGCUGCACUGCGGAAUCCGGCCUAAAGGAAGAGGCAACCAGGUGCAGCACCCAAGCCCAGGUGCCAGUCAUUUGCCGCUGGGCUCUCAGACCCAUUCUCCUUUUGCGGCUGUCACAUAUUCUGUAGGGAUUCUGAGCCCUGCCCUCUGUCAUCUUGUCCACUGGCUUCUCCUGCUUUCCACCACUGGGUGGGCUUGGAGGGUGGGAGGCAGGGAGAAGCCAGGGGGACUCUCAUCCCCUACUUUGGAAGAUGUCUGCCGCAGUAGUUGCACUAACUUUGUGGCUCCAACUCCUAUUGGACAAGCCCUCCAGGGUUCCGGCUGUCUCCUCUCUUUGCCCCUCCAGCCUCAGGGGAGAAGGCACGUCCAGCAGUUGCUAAUCUCAGGAUUGCCUCACCUUACCCUAGUUGAACGUCCAGUUCUUUCAACACUUGUAACUAAUUUGCUGCAUUAAAUUAUUGCUAUUGACUCGCUUGGGAAAGAAUACUUUCGCUGGAUUCACUUGCAGAGUUCAAAGACACUUUUCCUAAUGGGACUGCAAGCAGCGCAUCGGAGAAAAAAAUCUAGCAGUCCCAGGAGUCAAGAAGGGUCAGGGUCUACUUCAGUGUGUGAUCAGACAGCGACAAACCCACACUACCUAACAGGGCCGGAAGGCUCUUAGCCUAGGAAUUAGCUGUAAAAUGACUGGGUUCAUGUCUACUUUUUCAUGAUUUACUCUAUUCUCUUUGAUCACCGCCAGCCUUGGCUUAAGGAACAUCUCUGUAGAAUUCAAUUUUAUUCCUCAAGGGUUACUUAAGUGCCCAUUAUGAGUAUGGAGGGCACAUAGCUAGGUGUGGUGGGGAGGAGAUAUAGAGACGCAGGAAAAAUGGAGGGCAUGCUCAGUUUUUGGAAGUGUUUGCUUCCUGCAAGAUGAGGUUUGCGGACCUAUCAGGAGAGCCUCUUGAUAAAGACUCCUGAACUUUUCCAGUCUCACCAGAGCUGCAGACACUCGGAGGCAAUAUUAGUCUUACAGCUUUCAUUUCUCCCAUCACCAGAGCUCUGUUAAAAGCAGACUCCUCUUUAAGGAAUCCACAGAUCAGAGAGGGUACAGCACAUGCACACAACUGACCCCCAGGUCAGAAUGAUGCCAGCCACAAGGGGGGAUUCUGCUUGGGGGAGCAGGAAGACUGCACAGAGAUGGUAGGAGACGGCUACAGGAGCUGAGUCCAACAAAGUUUGACAGGUGGAGGCGGCUAAGGGGUAUUCUGGCAGAGAACAGAGAAGGAUCAAAAUAAAGUGUCAAAGGACAGACACAUUUCAGGUGUUGUCUGUAAACGGAGGCUUUGGGGUGAGGGUAGGGAAGUGGAGGGGAGACUGAAAAAUGGAGGCCCAGCUAUUGAGGACUCUGAGAAUGAGGCAUUAAGGCUCGAGGCCAUGGUGAGUCACUGGAGGAUCUUCAGCAUCAGGGCGGCAAGGUCACUUCUGGUGGGGUGGCGGGGGUGGGGUGGGGUGGGGGGACUUUGCGAUUAGAAGCAAAGAAGCUGGAGGCAGGAAAAGAAACUGCGAGCUCUCGGGUGGAGGGCAGCUUAUACGGGAAGCCUGGACUUGACCAUCGCCAGGGAGGCAUACUGACAUUCGAGCUGCCUUCCAUCUAUUCAAGGGCACGCUUCCUCCGUCUGUGGGGGGAGAAGGUGCCCCCUCAGAGGCUGUACGAUUCGAAGUCUCCGGCCUGAGAAGUUUCGAAUUUCUCCUUGCCAAGGUCGGGCCACUACAGACAUGGGAAAGCGGAACCACCAAAAGGAGUGAUGAUCAACGAUCUCAUGAUAAAUCUGGAUGCUAGUUCUCAUGCCUCAGGACAUCCUACUGGGAACGACACACCAGCUCCUGGGAUCAGACUUUCAUCUACUUAGGACCCCUCUUUGCCCAGACUACUAAAGCCAGUCUUCACUAGCCACGAAUGGCUACCCAAAGGAAACACUUGGUGAAAGAUUUUAAUCCUUACAUUACCUGCUAUAUCUGUAAAGGGUAUCUGAUCAAGCCAACAACAGUGACGGAAUGCCUCCAUACAUUCUGUAAGACUUGUAUUGUUCAGCACUUUGAAGAUAGCAAUGAUUGCCCAAGGUGUGGCAACCAAGUUCAUGAGACAAAUCCAUUAGAAAUGUUGAGGUUGGACAAUACAUUAGAGGAAAUUAUAUUUAAGCUGGUCCCUGGACUACGAGAACAAGAACUUGAGCGUGAAUCUGAAUUUUGGAAGAAAAAUAAGCCUCAAGAAAAUGGACAAGAUGAUACUUCAAAAGCUGACAAACCGAAAGUAGAUGAAGAAGGUGAUGAAAAUGAAGAUGAUAAAGAUUAUCACAGAAGUGACCCACAAAUUGCUAUCUGUCUAGAUUGUUUACGAAAUAAUGGGCAAUCAGGGGACAAUGUAGUAAAGGGUUUAAUGAAGAAAUUCAUUCGAUGUUCUACACGUGUAACUGUGGGAACUAUUAAAAAAUUUCUAAGUUUAAAACUAAAACUUCCAAGUUCUUAUGAGUUGGAUGUGCUGUGCAAUGGUGAAAUUAUGGGGAAGGAUCAUACUAUGGAAUUCAUCUACAUGACAAGAUGGCGACUAAGAGGCGAAAACUUUCGGUGUCUGAACUGCUCAGCUUCGCAAGUCUGCUCUCAGGAUGGCCCUUUGUAUCAGUCAUACCCUAUGGUACUGCAGUAUCGACCAAGAAUUGAUUUCGGUUAGACCAAGGGGCCCAGACCUCACUGAGAUGAAUCCUGCACUAUUUGUUUACUCGUCAACAGAUUGCACAGUUAACGGUGUGUGGACUAGAGGAACACAACCAGAUUUUCAGCAUGCAAAUAAGGCCAUUGUCUAUCUCUAAAUUGUCAGUUGCAUUCAUGUUGUUUCUAUUAGGAGCAAACCAAGUGCCAUUCUGCUACUGAACCAUCUGCAUAAGGUAUUUGUGUUGUCUCAAAGUGUGCAAGUCAUGGUAAAAAUCAGUUAGCUGUGCCGCCAUGAUUCACCCUUCUGAAUAUUUUGCUUGCCUGUUCCAAGAUUGUUCUAAUGUUUAAUUACACUAGUAAAAUGGCUCAAUUUUUGUGGUGUUGCAGUUUUCACAUACUUACUCUUUUAUUCUUGUUUAAAUAGCGUACUCUACAAGAAACUAAUAAUUAUAUCUUGAAAUUAUUUUGUAUGGAAGUAUAUUUAGAAAAGUGGUUUUUGAGCCACUGUCUUGUUCUUGAUAAGCUUUUUGUGUGAAAAAAAGUUCAUUCUUGAGUGUGCAAGUCCUUUUGCCAAGAAUUCCAAUUAUUCUGUAACAUUAGAGCACAAUAUAAUUGUAGACAUUCUAAGCAUCUGUCCGUGUAGUCUACCAAUUGCACAAGGAAGGCAUGUUAGCCCUCCAGAUUGAAAAUGUAUGUGACCUCUUGAACUGAAGUUAGAUUCCCAACCAUUCAAAAUGUUGGCAGCUGAUCACAUUUACUUCUGAUAAAAGUAAUGUGUAAGUAAGGUUAAUCUUCUUUCAUAAUGCCUUAUGACAAGCAGGUGCUGCUUCAUGAAACGUCAUUGUAUAGCCCAUUUCAUGUAUCAUUACAUUGUUGCUGUUAUUUAAUGAGUGCAUUAUUUCUCUUUUUAAGUUGGCCUUAGGUAUAUGUCAUUGUGGCAUGCAGAGGGUUAUGACGAUUUUAAAUAUUAGGAUUUUUAGAGCACAUAACAUUAGCUAUUUUAUGGAUUUCAAAAGUCUCAAAACAGUUGUAGAUUAAAACUGUUAGUUACCUUUCACAUUUCCAAACUAUGUGCAUAAAAUAGAAUAAAUGCAGUAUAGAACUAUGCUAACCAAAAUUAAUAGGUUAAGGGUAUUUUAUUUUAAAUCCUGUAGUAAUUGGGGAAAUGAGAAGAUUAUUAUUUUAUACAUGAGUUCAUUAAGAUCAGAAAUACAAAAUGUCCUGUAUUUUGCAGUUUUGUUAAGUCUUCCAUUCGUUUUAGGAUUAGUCUGCAAGUCAAAGAAAGUCUUGUUACCUUAAAUUAUAUGAAAACUGUCAUUUUAAAUCUUUUAAUAUUUACAGUUUUCAAAAACCUUACUUGGAAAUUGCUUUGAAACAAACAAGCUAACCUUUGAAACUUAGGAAAAAAUCUUGAAAGUUAGGAAAAAUAUUUGAGAAAUAUGACGAGCACAAUCUGUGUGUUACACACAUUUAGUUUUUAUACUGCAUAUGUGGUAAAUGUGUCACAUUUUCCAGUAAAAUGUAUCAGAAAUCAAUGCCUUCUGAAUUUCAAAAUGAUUCUUAGAAAUAAGAUAUUGUACAACUCUAGCAAACAUACAAAGUACAGCUAAAUCUUAAUAUAUUUCACUAUGUAAAAGGCUGAAACUUCAUAAUUAUCUGUUCCUUCUAUCUUUUUUUGAGUCAAAAAGUCUAUUAAAUUUUUCUGUUGUUGUUCCAACUUUGGUGAAAAAGGUUAUGGCAAUACUUUAACUUUGUUUUGUUACAUUGUUUUUGUUCUUGGAAUGGCUCACAAGCAGAAUUUAAAAGGCAGAUUUUCAUUAACUAUAAAUGGCUGAAAAAACUGAAUUUACUAUCUAGCUACAGAAAUUAUUUUUCUAUGGUGUGAAACUGUUCCCAGACAUCCCUAAGAACUUUUACAAAUUAUUAUAAAUUUGUCACACCUAGGUCAGCGAUUAAAAUAGUGUUUUGCAAAUGGAAUUUUAAUUAACUCAAAAUGAAUUAAGAGUGCAUUUUAAAAAUCACAAGUGAGACUUUGAUGUUUUGGCCCCCCAGCCAAAACUUAAUGGUCAUAAAUGAAUUUUAUCUACAAAAUCUCUUUAAAUUUGGCUGGUUGCCUUGUCAUAUGUAAUUUCACUAUUUUCCAAGGAAAUAUAUAGGAAGCAAUUAUGAAACUGAGAAUAGUUUUAUAUAGAAUUCUUUUAUUUACUGAUAAUGCAUUAACAUUUUUAUUGAAAUGCAAUGGAAUAUGUGCCAAAACACGUGAAAAGCUUACAUAAAGAAAGGCAUCAGUUGUCGUUUGGAGAAAGGUACACAUUUUUUUGAUGGUCCUAAGUGAUAUGGUAUUACUACUAGAAUCACAGAUUUCUUCAACUGACUUAUUUUGGUAUAUUCAACUACAGCUUUCUAAGGAUAGGACUACUUUCAUGUCUAGUAAUACACUGUAUUCCCCGUUAAUUAUCCCUUAAGUCAGAUUGUAGAAUUUGCAAGAAACUAGGUAUAGAAAAAAUGUACAGGCAACUUUUGUGGUUAGCUUUAUAAAUUUAGGGUGCUUAUAAAAUGAUAAAAUGAAUUCUUUAAAUAACCUAUAGGAAUCAUCUGAAUCUGUAACAUCAGAGACUAAAACUAAAAGUUUUCUUUAAUCUGUUGUUUCUUAAGCAAUAAACUGAAAGACCUUUACUUCCAUAAAAGAUUUUGUUAUCUCUUUUAUCUGCCUUAGAAAUUAUAAGUAUAAAAGGGUCAAGGGAACUUAGAUAUAAAGAAUGACUGUGGUUUAUAAACAUUACUUUAAUUGAAGUAAUCACAUCAGUUAAUAGAGAAAUCAAAAUAUGUAUGGCCUUUUCUCUAGAUUAGCAAAACAGCUUUACAAAGUAUGAAAAAAUAAACUAAAAUGCUCAUUGAUGAGGUAAUACUCAGUCUGGAGUACAGGUAACUUGGGUAAUGCCUUUUAACUACUCUUAGAGGAGUAUAUUAUUUCUUUAUACAUUAAACAUCUAUCCCAUAGUAAUGUGCCACAUUUUAUAAACGUAAUGACUUUGCUCAACUACAUUACACACUCAAAUGUAAUCUAAAUUUAAACUGAUUAUUUAAGGAAAAAAAGUGUGUUAUAUAAUAUUGUGAACUGUUUAGCUUUACUGAAAUAUUUAAGAGAAAGUGCCUCAUUACUAAAGUGCAUUUCUGUUUUAAAUUUACUGCAUAAAGUUUGAGUUAUCUGUACCUGUCUCUUAUGAAUGGUUUCAUAUCUAAAUAGGCUCUUGUAAGUUAAUUUUUUUGGAAGAUUUUCAUAAGAAUAUAGAUAUCACCAAAGACAUUUUACAGUAAAUUAAUAACCAUGUUGGAGAGACGGUUUUAACAGUUUGGAGGUUGGAAAUUUUUAGAUUGCAAUUUAAUUUUAUAUAGUUAGGCAAUAACCUUGAUUAAUUGCUAAAAUAUCACCAAAGAAAGGCUUUAAACUGAAUUUUCUUGGUGAGAUCAGUCAAAUGCAGGCUUUUCUUGCAAUAAUCAGAACACACUUCCUUUCAAAUAUGUUCAUUGUUUUUCAGCAUCAUCUAACAGAUCUUAGUAAAUCUAAAUCCUCAAAGAUGAGAAAGAGGUAAACACAACAAAUAGCCUUCCUCUGCAUGAAAAGUGAGAGAAAUACAUACUUUGAAAAGAAAGUUCAGAUUUUUAAUUUGAGAGGGUUUUUAUUUCAUGGAGGCAGUGUUAACUAAAAUUAAGCUUAGAUUUAGCUCCUGUAUUAUUCAUAAUAUGAGAAAUUUUAUUAAAGGCAGACUUUGGUAAAAGUGCCAACACACUUACUUGUAUAGAAAAGACUUCAUUCUAUGGGAUUUAUAUAAGUAAGUGCUUUCUCUAUAUUCAAAAUAUUUCAUAAGGACCUGUGGUUUUUUUCCCCUUAAAAAGCAACUCUAGGCCGGGCACAGUGGCUCAUGCCUGUAAUCCCAGCACUUUGGGAGGCCAAGGCAGGUGGAUCACUUGAGGUCAGGAGUUCGAGACCAGCUGGUUAACAUGGUGAAACCCCAUCUCUACUAAAAAUACAAAAAUUAGCCAGGUGUGGUGGCACGCGCCUGUAAUCCCAGCUACAUGGGAGGUUGAGGCAGGAGAAUCUCUUGAACCCAGGAGGUGGAGGUUGCAGUGAGCCGCAAUUACACCACUGCACUCCAGCCUGGGUGACACAGCGAGUCUCCAUCUCCAAAAAAAAUUCAACUCUUGGUCUUGUUUCUCAGCACUUAGUUUAUUGUUAUUAGAAUUUAGCCAUACAGCCAACUUUGACAAAAUGGGUCACAGAACAAGCAUGUACAUCAAGAGGAAGUUCCAUAUCCCCCUUGUACCAUUUCUCCUUGGGAACUCAUGCUAUGGGCUACCUUAAAGGUAAAACUCAUCUUAUGGAGUCUUUCUGAUAGGUCACUAGGUAAAACUCCUUGGAUAGGGUGAAAAUGGAUGCACACUCUAUUACAUACUCUGGUUUAUCAUAAGGAAUUUUCCAGAAAGCUAAGCUUUAUACUAAUAAGAUAUUGGUUGGUAGUAGGAACUUCAAAAAUGAAUGAGUUUGCCAUAACUUUAAUUUUCUGGAUUAGAAACACAAAACUUGAAAUGCAAUUAUCAAUAUUUUGUAAUAUAUAUUCCUACAGUUUGGGUAGAAAUAAGGAACAUGUCUGCUAGAUCUGGUUUAUGAAAAAGUGAAAAAUAUUAAAUACACCAGAGACUCAAACCCUUUCAAGGCACACAAUAACUGUUCUGGAUUUACCUGACAAACCUAGUUGAGUAGCAUUUUGACAGAAAAUAUCAGACUGAAAGUUCAUUCAAAUGUACUUAAAUGUACAAUACAGUGUUCAAUAGUUUUUAUUGCAGUGAUGUUUUUCCAAUAAUUUAAGUAAUUCUCUUCCUAGUAUAAUACAGUUUUCAUAAAUAAUGUUUACUUGCUUUCUUUAUAUUUUCAAAUAAAAUUAAAAUGCUCGAGCACUUCCUUUCAGAAAGUUAUAAAAUUAAAAAUAAUUAUUUUAAAUGCUCAUUCAAAUGUGUCUGUAUACUUGCUAUGCCCCUUUUUCUAUAAUUCCAAACUGAGACUGAUUUUUCAGAGAUUUUUAACUUUAAUAAUUUUAAAUCUAGAAUCAAGUGAAACAGAUAUGUUAAAUACUGAGUCUAGUUUUCUUCCAUCUUAUGGAGCUUCAUGGAAUAAGAAACUAAUCUAGUGCAAAUGAAGAUUAAAUAUUUCUGGGUGAUGGAGAGAUAGUCAACAAAUUUAUUUAUCCAUCCUCUGCACAUCAGUCCACUGGAGCAGGAGUUCUACACAUUAAAAAUGUAAUGGGAUCAGCCUAGCAUUGUUUGGUGUUCUUUUGUUGUAUUUUUUAGAAUGGGGGUGGGGGCCUAAGUGUCCUUAUGAAGCUGUGGUCCACGACAGGAGCUUGUUGGGGGAGUACCAGGGUUCUGCUGCUUUCCUGCAUCUGAGCAACACAACAGAGAUCAUCAGUUUUAAAUAGAGUAGCCCUCACAAUCAAAAUAUCAUAGAAUAUAUUGUAAAGUUAUGUUGCUAAUUUUCCUUUGAAAUAUAAAAUAUUUUAAGCUUUUUGUCAAAAGUGGUAACAUCUUAAUACAAAUAAAAACCUUUUUGUGGUUGUAAGAUUUAGCUUAUAAAUCAUUCAAAUUGAAGUGAAAGAAUUACCAGGUCAUUGUUAAUGACUUAGUCUAUUAAGAAUAUAUGUAUUUUUGUAAAGGAAAAGCACUUGUAGAUAUUUAAUCAGUACAAGAUAUGUCUUUUGCAGAAAUAAAAUGCUGCUUAGAGAUUCUCCUUAAAUAUUUUUUAUUUUUGUGCUCAAAUGUAUUUUCUGUUGAUCUAUGGAAUGUUCUGUACAAAGCUGUAUAAUUGUACUGUUGGGCUAGAUACUUUUUUUUUUUAAUCUGGACUUAGCCAAGUAUAUUUCACCAUGUUAAAAUACAGUAUCUUUGUUAUUAAAAAUUAAAUUGCAUAAUUUAUUAUUGUUUGUCAUCUUUAAUAUUAGUCACUGUAGAUUGCAGCCUUCAUUAAAAAUAUCUCCUUUAAGUACUA